AGCCGGGUUGUGGGAGGCUGUUGACCUUGAAUUAUGCCGAGCGACGCCUACAAACCCACCGCUCAGGCCUUCACCAGGAUUGUUCCCAUUCCACUUCCUUGCCCAGUCUUAGGCUUCAUUCCUUUUUCUUGCUAACGCUGCUUCCUCACCCUCUCUUGUCUCUGCGUCUUCUUUUUCCAUUUGUCCCUGGCAGCCAUCCGCAGAGAGAAGACCUUCCAGAAACAACAGGCUUCCCUUUCCUAAAGUUCUGCUGCCUUCUCUCAUUUUCAAAAUUAACCCCAAACUCCUUAGGGUGGCAUUCAUUUUUGUGACCUCUCCAGUUUCUAGCCAACACUAGGAAAGGGCAUUGCCAGGCCAGAACACACUGUGCCCUCUGAAGACCACACGCCCUUUACCACCUGUGCCCUUUGCUUGGAAUGCUUUUUCUUCCCUUUCUCCUUGUUUGCCUGCCUAGCUCCUACUCAUCCUCUUAGCUUCAUAUCCUUUGUGAUGUCAUCCUUGAUUCCCCUUCAGGCAAAGUGAGUGGUUCCCUUCUCUAUGUUCCUGCAACAUUUUUUUCCUACCUCAGUCAUAGUUUUUGUAACAUUAUGUUGUAAUUUUCUCUCUCUGUCUUCCUCCAUCAUACUGGGAACUUCUGGAGGGCAGCACUUCUUGUGAUUCAUCACUGUGUCCUCUGUACCCGGCAACAACACAGCAUAGGGCCAGACACGUAGUGGUUGCCUUACUCAUUUAUUGAAUGCUCUGCUAAUUGUCAGGUGCGCUGCUAAAAAUUUUGGAGGCAUUAAUUCACCUUCUAAGAUUCUGCUGAAGUGAUCCAGUCUCGAGUGAACGACCAGGAGGGCCGAGAGGAAUUCUAUGUACACUACGUGGGCUUUAACCGGCGGCUGGACGAGUGGGUAGACAAGAACCGGCUGGCGCUGACCAAGACAGUGAAGGAUGCUGUACAGAAGAACUCAGAGAAGUACCUGAGCGAGCUCGCAGAGCAGCCUGAGCGCAAGAUCACUCGCAACCAAAAGCGCAAGCAUGAUGAGAUCAACCAUGUGCAGAAGACUUAUGCAGAGAUGGACCCCACCACAGCAGCCUUGGAGAAGGAGCAUGAGGCGAUCACCAAGGUGAAGUAUGUGGACAAGAUCCACAUCGGGAACUACGAAAUUGAUGCCUGGUAUUUCUCACCAUUCCCCGAAGACUAUGGGAAACAGCCCAAGCUCUGGCUCUGCGAGUACUGCCUCAAGUACAUGAAAUAUGAGAAGAGCUACCGCUUCCACUUGGGUCAGUGCCAGUGGCGGCAGCCCCCCGGGAAAGAGAUCUACCGCAAGAGCAACAUCUCCGUGUACGAAGUUGAUGGCAAAGACCAUAAGAUUUACUGUCAGAACCUGUGUCUGCUGGCCAAGCUUUUCCUGGACCAUAAGACACUGUACUUUGACGUGGAGCCGUUCGUCUUUUACAUCCUGACUGAGGUGGACCGGCAGGGGGCCCACAUUGUUGGCUACUUCUCCAAGGAGAAGGAGUCCCCGGAUGGAAACAAUGUGGCCUGCAUCCUGACCUUGCCCCCCUACCAACGCCGCGGCUACGGGAAGUUCCUCAUCGCUUUCAGUUAUGAGCUCUCCAAGCUGGAGAGCACAGUCGGCUCCCCGGAGAAGCCACUGUCUGACCUGGGCAAGCUCAGCUACCGCAGCUACUGGUCCUGGGUGCUGCUAGAGAUCCUGCGGGACUUCCGGGGCACACUGUCCAUCAAGGACCUCAGCCAGAUGACCAGUAUCACCCAAAAUGACAUCAUCAGUACCCUGCAAUCCCUCAAUAUGGUCAAGUACUGGAAGGGCCAGCACGUGAUCUGUGUCACACCCAAGCUGGUGGAGGAGCACCUCAAAAGUGCCCAGUAUAAGAAACCACCCAUCACAGUGGACUCCGUCUGCCUCAAGUGGGCACCCCCCAAGCACAAGCAAGUCAAGCUCUCCAAGAAGUGAGCAGCCUGGCCCCUGCUGUCGGACCUGAGCCUCCUGGCUCCCAGCCUGUAAAUAUGUAUAGACCUGUUUUGUCAUUUUUUUAAUAAAGUCAGUUCUGGUG